GUCAAGGCCGUUCCUUCAGUGUUUUCAGACGCCCUGGGAACGCGGCUGCAGGGUCCGGUCUUCGGUUUGCACAGCUAGAGGCCGCGCAGCAGCAAAGGAUGAGCGGAACCUUGGAAAAGGCUGGUCUGGAACUCCUGGAAAAGAGCCCAUGGAAAUCUGUCAUUAAGGCCAGCAUCUGACAUGGGUAUAUAAGGCCUCUCGACGUCUGAUGCCACUGUUCUCUUCCCGACUCCUUAGUUGCUUUAGUCAGCUAACCUCGUCAUUAUUUGCCAAAUGUGCUGUGCCUGAGGAACAAUACCAUUUUUAAGCAAGCCUUUUCUCUCUUAAGGUUUAGAACUUCAGGAGAGAAGCCCAUCUAUUCUGUAGAGAGAGACGGUCUUGCUUGUGGCCCAGGCUUGAGUACAGUGGCAUGAUCAUAGCUCCCUGCAGCCUCGAACUCCUGGGUUCAAGCAAUCCUCCUGCCUCAGCCUCUGGAGUAGCUGGGAUUACAGGUGGAAUUCUACUAAGUAUCAGUCGGCCCUACAAGACAAAGCCCACCCACGGCAUUGGAAAGUACAAGCACUUAAUUAAAGCAGAAGAGCCCAAGAAGAAGAAGGGAAAAGUGGAAGUGAGAGCCAUUAAUUUGGGGACAGAUUAUGAAUAUGGGGUUUUAAAUAUUCAUCUGACUGCAUAUGAUAUGACCCUGGCAGAGAGUUAUGCCCAGUAUGUUCACAACCUCUGCAACUCUCUCUCCAUUAAAGUCGAGGAAAGUUAUGCAAUGCCAACCAAAACCAUAGAAGUGUUGCAGUUGCAGGACCAAGGCAGCAAAAUGCUCCUGGACUCAGUGCUUACCACCCAUGAGCGAGUGGUUCAGAUCAGCGGUUUGAGUGCUACGUUUGCAGAAAUUUUCUUGGAAAUAAUCCAAAGCAGUCUUCCUGAAGGAGUCAGACUGUCAGUGAAGGAGCACACUGAAGAAGACUUCAAGGGACGAUUCAAAGCUCGACCAGAACUGGAAGAACUGUUGGCCAAGUUGAAGUAGCUACUGUAGACCCUUUCAUGCCAGCAGUGGUCAUAUUGAGUGCCAAAGAGAAGAGCUUACUGGGUAGUUAGAGUUCAUCAGGAGACCCAACCCUUAGAUUUCAUAAGUACCCAUUCCCAUAGCCAGUAAUGUCCUCACUCCUCUGUGGCUUGGCUGUACUUGCCAUUUCUUACCACUUACCUAUGAGGUAAUGCUUGUUAUCUUCCAUCUAAUAAAAAUCUGCUGCAGAUGUGUAUAUGUAUGUGUGUGUGAGAGAGAGAAAUUGGCCCAUCCUGUGGAGUAUCUUUAAGAGAUUCUAUAUUCUGGCCAGGCACCGUGGUGCAUCCCUGUAAUCCCAGCACUUUGCGAGGCCGAGGCAGGAGGACUGCUCGAGGCCAGGAGCUUGAGACCAGCCUGGCAACAUUCUGUCUUUACCAAAAACAUUCUUUUUUUUUUUUCCGAAACGGAGUCUCGCUCUGUUGCCCAGGCUGGAGUGCAGUGGCACGAUCUAGACUCACUGCAAGCUCUGCCUCCCGGGUUCACACCAUUCUCCUGCCUCAGCCUCCCAAGUAGCUGGGACUGCAGGCGCCCGCCACCACACCUGGCUAAUUUUUUGUAUUUUUAGUAGAGACGGGGUUUUACCAUGUUAGCCAAGAUGGUCUCGAUCUCCUGACCUCGUGAUCCGCCAGCCUUGGCCUCCCAAAGUGCUGGGAUUACAGGUGUGAGCCACUGCACCCAGCCAAACUUUUUAUUUUAAUUAGCUGGACGUGGUGGUAUGCACUUG